AGCCCUGCAGCGCCUUCCUGGAGGUGGGGGCCGCCCGCGCCAUGGCCGCCGCCCAGCCCAAGUACCCCGCCGGGGCGACCGCCCGGCGCCUGGCCCGGGGCUGCUGGUCCGCCCUCUGGGACUACGAGACGCCCAAGGUGAUCGUGGUGAGGAACCGGCGCCUGGGGGUCCUGUACCGCGCCGUGCAGCUGCUCAUCCUGCUCUACUUCGUGUGGUACGUAUUCAUCGUGCAGAAAAGCUACCAGGAGAGCGAGACGGGCCCCGAGAGCUCCAUCAUCACCAAGGUCAAGGGGAUCACCACGUCCGAGCACAAAGUGUGGGACGUGGAGGAGUACGUGAAGCCCCCCGAGGGGGGCAGCGUGUUCAGCAUCAUCACCAGGGUCGAGGCCACCCACUCCCAGACCCAGGGAACCUGCCCCGAGAGCAUAAGGGUCCACAACGCCACCUGCCUCUCCGACGCCGACUGCGUGGCUGGGGAGCUGGACAUGCUGGGAAACGGCCUGAGGACUGGGCGCUGUGUGCCCUAUUACCAGGGGCCCUCCAAGACCUGCGAGGUGUUCGGCUGGUGCCCGGUGGAAGAUGGGGCCUCUGUCAGCCAAUUUCUGGGUACGAUGGCCCCAAAUUUCACCAUCCUCAUCAAGAACAGCAUCCACUACCCCAAAUUCCACUUCUCCAAGGGCAACAUCGCCGACCGCACAGACGGGUACCUGAAGCGCUGCACGUUCCACGAGGCCUCCGACCUCUACUGCCCCAUCUUCAAGCUGGGCUUUAUCGUGGAGAAGGCUGGGGAGAGCUUCACAGAGCUCGCACACAAGGGUGGUGUCAUCGGGGUCAUUAUCAACUGGGACUGUGACCUGGACCUGCCUGCAUCGGAGUGCAACCCCAAGUACUCCUUCCGGAGGCUUGACCCCAAGCACGUGCCUGCCUCGUCAGGCUACAACUUCAGGUGCUGUACUUGGGACACCGCUGUCCACACUGGCAUAGCUGUGGUGGGGUCCCGAGAGGCCCAAUGCCUGUGGGGCAGCCCUGGAGUGCAGAGGACGAGUGGGCACUGGCGUUCCCAUUGCAGGUUUGCCAAAUACUACAAGAUCAAUGGCACCACCACCCGCACGCUCAUCAAGGCCUACGGGAUCCGCAUUGACGUCAUUGUGCAUGGACAGGCCGGGAAGUUCAGCCUGAUUCCCACCAUUAUUAAUCUGGCCACAGCUCUGACUUCCGUCGGGGUGGGCUCCUUCCUGUGCGACUGGAUCUUGCUAACAUUCAUGAACAAAAACAAGGUCUACAGCCAUAAGAAAUUUGACAAGGUGUGUACGCCGAGCCACCCCUCAGGUAGCUGGCCUGUGACCCUUGCCCGUGUAUUGGGCCAGGCCCCUCCCGAACCCGGCCACCGCUCCGAGGACCAGCACCCCAGCCCUCCAUCAGGCCAGGAGGGCCAACAAGGGGCAGAGUGUGGCCCAGCCUUCCCGCCCCUGCGGCCUUGCCCCAUCUCUGCCCCUUCUGAGCAGAUGGUGGACACUCCUGCCUCCGAGCCUGCCCAAGCCUCCACACCCACAGACCCCAAAGGUUUGGCUCAACUCUGAGCUCCUUUCCAUCUCACUGGACUGCAGACCCGGCCUGGUGGGGCCAGAGAGUCCCCAGCUAGGGACCUGCACGUGGACGUGGGCACCUCAGUAGCGGAGCAUCUCCACGAAACGGGGCACCACAGGAUCCCUGUGCAAGGGCUGGGGGCACGCUCUGGCCCCAGGCUUGUGCCCCACCCUGGCAUACAGCCCCUGACACCUCCUCCCCAGCUGGUCCCUACAGGGCUGCUCACUUCCCAUCACCUCUCACAGCCACCUGGAACCCAAGCCAGCUGAGCUCUGAGGGGCUCUGCUCCCGGUCUUGGGCCCUGGGAACCCCACCCCACCCCACCCCACAGGCGUUGUAACCUUGAAUCUGCCCAGACUCUUCCCUUAGAAGUCACAACAUACUCAGUCCAAUAAACCUGUGAGCAGAA